AUGACCCACCAAUCACAUGCCUAUCAUAUAGUAAAACCCAGCCCAUGACCCCUAACAGGGGCCCUCUCAGCCCUCCUAAUGACCUCCGGCCUAGCCAUGUGAUUUCACUUCCACUCCAUAACGCUCCUCAUACUAGGCCUACUAACCAACACACUAACCAUAUACCAAUGAUGGCGCGAUGUAACACGAGAAAGCACAUACCAAGGCCACCACACACCACCUGUCCAAAAAGGCCUUCGAUACGGGAUAAUCCUAUUUAUUACCUCAGAAGUUUUUUUCUUCGCAGGAUUUUUCUGAGCCUUUUACCACUCCAGCCUAGCCCCUACCCCCCAAUUAGGAGGGCACUGGCCCCCAACAGGCAUCACCCCGCUAAAUCCCCUAGAAGUCCCACUCCUAAACACAUCCGUAUUACUCGCAUCAGGAGUAUCAAUCACCUGAGCUCACCAUAGUCUAAUAGAAAACAACCGAAACCAAAUAAUUCAAGCACUGCUUAUUACAAUUUUACUGGGUCUCUAUUUUACCCUCCUACAAGCCUCAGAGUACUUCGAGUCUCCCUUCACCAUUUCCGACGGCAUCUACGGCUCAACAUUUUUUGUAGCCACAGGCUUCCACGGACUUCACGUCAUUAUUGGCUCAACUUUCCUCACUAUCUGCUUCAUCCGCCAACUAAUAUUUCACUUUACAUCCAAACAUCACUUUGGCUUCGAAGCCGCCGCCUGAUACUGGCAUUUUGUAGAUGUGGUUUGACUAUUUCUGUAUGUCUCCAUCUAUUGAUGAGGGUCUU